AUGGGGGACUGGAACUUAUUGGGUGGCAUCCUAGAGGAAGUUCACUCCCACUCAACCAUAGUGGGGAAAAUCUGGCUGACCAUCCUCUUCAUCUUCCGAAUGCUGGUACUUCGUGUGGCUGCUGAGGAUGUCUGGGAUGAUGAACAGUCAGCAUUUGCCUGCAACACCCGGCAGCCAGGUUGCAACAAUAUCUGUUAUGAUGAUGCAUUCCCUAUCUCUUUGAUCAGGUUCUGGGUUUUACAGAUCAUCUUUGUGUCUUCUCCUUCUUUGGUCUAUAUGGGCCAUGCACUUUAUAGGCUCAGGGCCUUUGAGAAAGACAGGCAGAGGAAAAAGUCACACCUUAGAGCCCAGAUGGAGAAUCCAGAUCUUGACUUGGAGGAGCAGCAAAGAAUAGAUAGGGAACUGAGGAGGUUAGAGGAGCAGAAGAGGAUCCAUAAAGUCCCUCUGAAAGGAUGUCUGCUGCGUACUUAUGUCUUACACAUCUUGACCAGAUCUGUGCUGGAAGUAGGAUUCAUGAUAGGCCAAUAUAUUCUCUAUGGGUUUCAAAUGCACCCCCUUUACAAAUGCACUCAACCUCCUUGCCCCAAUGCGGUGGAUUGCUUUGUAUCCAGGCCCACUGAGAAGACAAUUUUCAUGCUUUUUAUGCACAGCAUUGCAGCCAUUUCCUUGUUACUCAAUAUACUGGAAAUAUUUCAUCUAGGCAUCAGAAAAAUUAUGAGGACACUUUAUAAGAAAUCCAGCAGUGAGGGCAUUGAGGAUGAAACAGGCCCUCCAUUCCAUUUGAAGAAAUAUUCUGUGGCCCAGCAGUGUAUGAUUUGCUCUUCAUUGCCUGAAAGAAUCUCUCCACUUCAAGCUAACAAUCAACAGCAAGUCAUUCGAGUUAAUGUGCCAAAGUCUAAAACCAUGUGGCAAAUCCCACAGCCAAGGCAACUUGAAGUAGACCCUUCCAAUGGGAAAAAGGACUGGUCUGAGAAGGAUCAGCAUAGCGGACAGCUCCAUGUUCACAGCCCGUGUCCCUGGGCUGGCAGUGCUGGAAAUCAGCACCUGGGACAGCAAUCAGACCAUUCCUCAUUUGGCCUGCAGAAUACAAUGUCUCAGUCCUGGCUAGGUACAACUACGGCUCCUAGAAACUGUCCAUCCUUUGCAGUAGGAACCUGGGAGCAGUCCCAGGACCCAGAACCCUCAGGUGAGCCUCUCACAGAUCUUCAUAGUCACUGCAGAGACAGUGAAGGCAGCAUGAGAGAGAGUGGGGUCUGGAUAGACAGAUCUCGCCCAGGCAGUCGCAAGGCCAGCUUUCUGUCCAGAUUGUUGUCUGAAAAGCGACAUCUGCACAGUGACUCAGGAAGCUCUGGUUCUCGGAAUAGCUCCUGCUUGGAUUUUCCUCACUGGGAAAACAGCCCCUCACCUCUGCCUUCAGUCACUGGGCACAGAACAUCAAUGGUAAGACAGGCAGCCCUACCGAUCAUGGAACUAUCACAAGAGCUGUUCCAUUCUGGAUGCUUUCUUUUUCCUUUCUUUCUUCCUGGGGUGUGUAUGUAUGUUUGUGUUGACAGAGAGGCAGAUGGAGGGGGAGAUUAUUUAUGGAGAGAUAAAAUUAUUCAUUCGAUACAUUCAGUUAAAUUCAAUUCAUAAAAUAGACUUAGAAAAAUCUU